GCCACAAGCCUCCACCCCAGCUGGUCCCCCACCCAGGCUGCCCAGUUUAACAUUCCUAGUCAUAGGACCUUGACUUCUGAGAGGCCUGAUUGUCAUCUGUAAAUAAGGGGUAGGACUAAAGCACUCCUCCUGGAGGACUGAGAGAUGGGCUGGACCGGAGCACUUGAGUCUGGGAUAUGUGACCAUGCUACCUUUGUCUCCCUGUCCUGUUCCUUCCCCCAGCCCCAAAUCCAGGGUUUUCCAAAGUGUGGUUCAAGAACCACCUGCAUCUGAAUCUAGAGGUACUGGAUACAACCCCACGUCUGGGCCGUUACCCAGGACAUUCUACAUGAGAACGUGGGGGUGGGGCCCUGGCUGCACCUGAACUGUCACCUGGAGUCAGGGUGGAAGGUGGAAGAACUGGGUCUUAUUUCCUUCUCCCCUUGUUCUUUAGGGUCUGUCCUUCUGCAGACUCCGUUACCCCACCCUAACCAUCCUGCACACCCUUGGAGCCCUCUGGGCCAAUGCCCUGUCCCGCAAAGGGCUUCUCAGGCAUCUCACCUCUAUGGGAGGGCAUUUUUGGCCCCCAGAACCUUACACGGUGUUUAUGUGGGGAAGCCCCUGGGAAGCAGACAGUCCUAGGGUGAAGCUGAGAGGCAGAGAGAAGGGGAGACAGACAGAGGGUGGGGCUUUCCCCCUUGUCUCCAGUGCCCUUUCUGGUGACCCUCGGUUCUUUUCCCCCACCACCCCCCCAGCGGAGCCCAUCGUGGUGAGGCUUAAGGAGGUCCGACUGCAGAGGGACGACUUCGAGAUUCUGAAGGUGAUCGGACGCGGGGCGUUCAGCGAGGUAGCGGUAGUGAAGAUGAAGCAGACGGGCCAGGUGUAUGCCAUGAAGAUCAUGAACAAGUGGGACAUGCUGAAGAGGGGCGAGGUGUCGUGCUUCCGUGAGGAGAGGGACGUGUUGGUGAAUGGGGACCGGCGGUGGAUCACGCAGCUGCACUUCGCCUUCCAGGAUGAGAACUACCUGUACCUGGUCAUGGAGUAUUACGUGGGCGGGGACCUGCUGACACUGCUGAGCAAGUUUGGGGAGCGGAUUCCGGCCGAGAUGGCGCGCUUCUACCUGGCGGAGAUUGUCAUGGCCAUAGACUCGGUGCACCGGCUUGGCUACGUGCACAGGGACAUCAAACCCGACAACAUCCUGCUGGACCGCUGUGGCCACAUCCGCCUGGCCGACUUCGGCUCUUGCCUCAAGCUGCGGGCAGAUGGAACGGUGCGGUCGCUGGUGGCUGUGGGCACCCCAGACUACCUGUCCCCCGAGAUCCUGCAGGCUGUGGGCGGUGGGCCUGGGACAGGCAGCUACGGGCCCGAGUGUGACUGGUGGGCGCUGGGUGUAUUCGCCUAUGAAAUGUUCUAUGGGCAGACGCCCUUCUACGCGGAUUCCACGGCGGAGACCUAUGGCAAGAUCGUCCACUACAAGGAGCACCUCUCUCUGCCGCUGGUGGACGAAGGGGUCCCUGAGGAGGCUCGAGACUUCAUUCAGCGGUUGCUGUGUCCCCCGGAGACACGGCUGGGCCGGGGUGGAGCAGGCGACUUCCGGACACAUCCCUUCUUCUUUGGCCUCGACUGGGAUGGUCUCCGGGACAGCGUGCCCCCCUUUACACCGGAUUUCGAAGGUGCCACCGACACAUGCAACUUCGACUUGGUGGAGGACGGGCUCACUGCCAUGGUGAGCGGGGGCGGGGAGACACUGUCGGACAUUCGGGAAGGUGCGCCGCUAGGGGUCCACCUGCCUUUUGUGGGCUACUCCUACUCCUGCAUGGCCCUCAGGGACAGUGAGGUCCCAGGCCCCACACCCAUGGAACUGGAGGCCGAGCAGCUGCUUGAGCCACACGUGCAAGCGCCCAGCCUGGAGCCCUCGGUGUCCCCACAGGAUGAAACAGCUGAAGUGGCAGUUCCAGCGGCUGUCCCUGCGGCAGAGGCUGAGGCCGAGGUGACGCUGCGGGAGCUCCAGGAAGCCCUGGAGGAGGAGGUGCUCACCCGGCAGAGCCUGAGCCGGGAGAUGGAGGCCAUCCGCACGGACAACCAGAACUUCGCCAGUCAACUACGCGAGGCAGAGGCUCGGAACCGGGACCUAGAGGCACACGUCCGGCAGUUGCAGGAGCGGAUGGAGUUGCUGCAGGCAGAGGGAGCCACAGCUGUCACGGGGGUCCCCAGUCCCCGGGCCACGGAUCCACCUUCCCAUCUAGAUGGCCCCCCGGCCGUGGCUGUGGGCCAGUGCCCGCUGGUGGGGCCAGGCCCCAUGCACCGCCGCCACCUGCUGCUCCCUGCCAGGGUCCCUAGGCCUGGCCUAUCGGAGGCGCUUUCCCUGCUCCUGUUCGCCGUUGUUCUGUCUCGUGCCGCCGCCCUGGGCUGCAUUGGGUUGGUGGCCCACGCCGGCCAACUCACCGCAGUCUGGCGCCGCCCAGGAGCCGCCCGCGCUCCCUGAACCCUAGAACUGUCUUCGACUCCGGGGCCCCGUUGGAAGACUGAGUGCCCGGGGCACGGCACAGAAGCCGCGCCCACCGCCUGCCAGUUCACAACCGCUCCGAGCGUGGGUCUCCGCCCAGCUCCAGUCCUGUGAUCCGGGCCCGCCCCCUAGCGGCCGGGGAGGGAGGGGCCGGGUCCGCGGCCGGCGAACGGGGCUCGAAGGGUCCUUGUAGCCGGGAAUGCUGCUGCUGCUGCUGCUGCUGCUGCUGCUGCUGCUGCUGCUGCUGCUGCUGCUGCUGCUGGGGGGAUCACAGACCAUUUCUUUCUUUCGGCCAGGCUGAGGCCCUGACGUGGAUGGGCAAACUGCAGGCCUGGGAAGGCAGCAAGCCGGGCCGUCCGUGUUCCAUCCUCCACGCACCCCCACCUAUCGUUGGUUCGCAAAGUGCAAAGCUUUCUUGUGCAUGACGCCCUGCUCUGGGGAGCGUCUGGCGCGAUCUCUGCCUGCUUACUCGGGAAAUUUGCUUUUGCCAAACCCGCUUUUUCGGGGAUCCCGCGCCCCCCUCCUCACUUGCGCUGCUCUCGGAGCCCCAGCCGGCUCCGCCCGCUUCGGCGGUUUGGAUAUUUAUUGACCUCGUCCUCCGACUCGCUGACAGGCUACAGGACCCCCAACAACCCCAAUCCACGUUUUGGAUGCACUGAGACCCCGACAUUCCUCGGUAUUUAUUGUCUGUCCCCACCUAGGACCCCCACCCCCGACCCUCGCGAAUAAAAGGCCCUCCAUCUGCCCAAAGCUCUGGA